AGGCGGCGCGCACGGUAUGGCGGCGGCGGCGGCGGCGGCGGCGCGCGCCUGAGAAGAGGGGACGCCAGCCCGGUCAGGCCUCGGCGCGGCCUACACGCUCCGCUCGCUCGCUCGCUCCCGCCUCCCGCCCCGCGCCCGGCCAUGGCGGAGCCGUCGUCCGCCCGACGCCCGGUGCCUCUCAUCGAGUCGGAGCUGUACUUCCUUAUCGCCCGGUACCUAUCGGCGGGCCCGUGUCGGAGAGCGGCCCAGGUGCUGGUGCAGGAGCUGGAGCAGUACCAGUUGUUGCCGAAGAGAUUGGACUGGGAGGGCAACGAGCACAACAGGAGCUACGAGGAGUUGGUCUUGUCCAAUAAGCAUGUGGCUCCUGAUCAUCUUUUGCAAAUCUGCCAGCGCAUCGGUCCUAUGUUGGAUAAAGAAAUUCCACCCAGUAUUUCAAGAGUCACUUCUUUACUUGGUGCAGGAAGGCAGUCUUUGCUACGUACAGCAAAAGACUGCAGGCACACAGUUUGGAAGGGCUCUGCCUUUGCUGCUCUUCAUAGAGGAAGACCUCCUGAAAUGCCAGUGAAUUAUGGUUCCCCACCAAAUCUUGUGGAGAUACAUCGAGGAAAACAACUCACAGGGUGUUCCACUUUUAGUACAGCAUUUCCAGGAACUAUGUAUCAGCAUAUAAAAAUGCACAGAAGGAUUCUCGGACAUCUAUCUGCUGUUUACUGUGUAGCAUUUGAUAGGACAGGACAUAGAAUCUUUACAGGUUCAGAUGACUGUUUGGUAAAGAUUUGGUCAACACAUAAUGGCCGCUUGUUAUCUACAUUAAGAGGUCAUUCUGCAGAAAUUUCAGAUAUGGCAGUAAACUAUGAGAAUACAAUGAUUGCUGCGGGGAGCUGUGAUAAAAUUAUUAGAGUGUGGUGCUUGAGAACUUGUGCCCCAGUUGCUGUGCUCCAAGGACACACAGGAUCAAUUACAUCUUUACAGUUUAGCCCGAUGGCCAAAGGCUCUCAAAGAUACAUGGUUUCCACUGGUGCUGAUGGGACAGUUUGCUUUUGGCAAUGGGAUUUAGAAUCCUUAAAAUUUAGCCCACGUCCCCUGAAGUUCACUGAAAAGCCUAGGCCAGGCGUUCAAAUGCUUUGUUCUUCUUUUAGUGUUGGUGGUAUGUUUUUAGCCACAGGUAGUACUGAUCAUGUAAUCAGAAUGUAUUUUUUGGGUUUUGAAGCACCCGAAAAAAUCGCAGAACUUGAAAGCCACACUGAUAAAGUAGAUAGUAUCCAAUUUUGUAACAAUGGUGAUCGGUUCCUAAGUGGUAGCAGAGAUGGAACAGCACGGAUUUGGAGAUUUGAGCAGUUAGAAUGGAGGAGCAUUUUAUUGGAUAUGGCUACCAGAAUCUCAGGGGACUUAUCUUCCGAAGAGGAAAGGUUUAUGAAACCUAAAGUAACAAUGAUAGCUUGGAAUCAAAAUGAUAGCAUUGUUGUCACAGCUGUGAAUGAUCAUGUCCUCAAAGUGUGGAAUUCUUACACUGGACAACUGCUUCAUAACUUAAUGGGACAUGCUGAUGAAGUAUUUGUUCUGGAGACACAUCCCUUUGAUUCCAGAAUUAUGUUAUCUGCAGGACAUGAUGGCAGCAUAUUUAUAUGGGAUAUUACAAAAGGUACCAAGAUGAAACAUUAUUUUAAUAUGAUUGAAGGACAAGGACAUGGAGCUGUGUUUGACUGUAAGUUUUCACAGGAUGGACAGCAUUUUGCCUGUACAGAUUCUCAUGGGCACCUUCUGAUAUUUGGUUUUGGAUGCAGCAAACCAUAUGAAAAGAUUCCUGAUCAGAUGUUCUUCCAUACUGACUAUCGACCACUUAUUAGAGAUUCUAAUAAUUAUGUCUUAGAUGAGCAAACUCAGCAGGCUCCUCAUCUUAUGCCUCCACCAUUCUUGGUAGAUGUAGAUGGAAAUCCUCAUCCAACCAAGUAUCAGAGAUUAGUACCAGGCCGAGAAAAUUCUGCAGAUGAACAUUUGAUUCCACAGCUGGGCUAUGUGGCAACAAGUGAUGGAGAGGUGAUUGAACAAAUUAUAAGCCUGCAAACCAAUGAUAAUGAUGAACGCAGCCCAGAAUCGAGUAUUCUUGAUGGAAUGAUAAGACAGUUGCAGCAGCAGCAAGAUCAGAGAAUGGGAGCAGAUCAGGAUACUAUUCCAAGAGGACUUUCAAAUGGUGAAGAAACACCCCGGAGAGGUUUUAGAAGGCUGAGCUUAGACAUUCAGUCCCCUCCAAAUAUUGGUCUGCGUCGUAGUGGACAAGUUGAAGGUGUUCGUCAGAUGCAUCAAAACGCUCCACGCAGUCAGAUUGCUACAGAACGUGACCUGCAGGCUUGGAAACGAAGAGUGGUUGUACCAGAGGUACCACUAGGCAUAUUUAGGAAGCUGGAAGACUUCCGAUUAGAGAAAGGUGAAGAGGAAAGAAAUCUUUAUAUAAUAGGAAGAAAAAGAAAGACUCUUCAGCUCUCACAUAAGUCGGAUUCAGUGGUUUUGGUAUCACAGUCUAGACAAAGGACAUGUAGGCGUAAAUAUCCAAAUUAUGGUAGAAGAAAUCGUAGCUGGCGUGAGUUAUCUUCUGGAAAUGAGUCUUCAAGCUCUGUAAGACAUGAGACUUCCUGUGAUCAGAGUGAAGGUUCUGGUUCUUCAGAAGAGGAUGAAUGGAGAAGUGACAGAAAAAGUGAGAGUUACAGCGAAAGUUCAAGUGACUCUUCAUCUAGAUAUUCCGAUUGGACAGCUGAUGCGGGCAUCAAUUUGCAGCCUCCUUUAAGAACAUCAUGUCGUCGACGAAUUACUCGAUUUUGUAGUAGUUCAGAAGAUGAAAUAUCUACUGAGAAUUUAUCUCCUCCAAAAAGAAGACGAAAGAGAAAGAAAGAAAAUAAGCCUAAGAAGGAGAAUUUGCGGAGGAUGACUCCAGCAGAGCUUGCAAAUAUGGAGCAUUUAUAUGAAUUUCACCCUCCAGUUUGGAUUACUGACACCACACUUAGAAAAUCUCCUUUUGUUCCUCAAAUGGGUGAUGAGGUAAUAUAUUUUCGACAGGGUCAUGAAGCUUAUAUUGAGGCUGUAAGAAGAAAUAAUAUUUAUGAACUGAACCCUAAUAAGGAGCCAUGGAGAAAAAUGGAUCUUAGGGAUCAAGAAUUGGUUAAAAUAGUUGGAAUACGAUAUGAAGUUGGGCCCCCUACACUCUGUUGCCUAAAACUAGCAUUUAUAGAUCCAGCAACUGGAAAACUUAUGGACAAAUCUUUCUCUAUUAGAUAUCAUGAUAUGCCAGAUGUUAUUGACUUUCUUGUAUUGCGUCAAUUUUAUGAUGAAGCAAGACAGAGGAAUUGGCAGUCUUGUGACAGAUUCCGCUCUAUUAUUGAUGAUGCUUGGUGGUUUGGAACAGUGUUAAGUCAAGAGCCAUAUCAACCACAGUAUCCUGAUAGUCAUUUCCAGUGUUAUAUUGUUAGGUGGGAUAAUACUGAAAUUGAAAAACUUAGCCCAUGGGACAUGGAACCAAUUCCUGAUAAUGUUGAUCCACCUGAAGAAUUAGGAGCUAGUAUUUCUGUCACAACAGAUGAGCUAGAGAAAUUGCUCUAUAAACCACAAGCUGGUGAAUGGGGUCAGAAAUCAAGAGAUGAAGAAUGUGAUAGAAUUAUCAGUGGUAUAGAUCAACUUUUGAAUCUUGAUAUAGCAGCAGCUUUUGCAGGCCCUGUUGAUUUGUGUACAUACCCGAAGUACUGUACUGUAGUAGCUUAUCCAACCGAUCUUUACACAAUUCGAAUGAGACUUGUUAAUCGAUUUUACAGGAGGCUGUCUGCGUUAGUUUGGGAAGUCAGAUAUAUAGAACAUAAUGCCAGAACAUUUAACGAACCUGAGAGUGUAAUUGCAAGAUCAGCUAAAAAGAUAACUGACCAACUUUUAAAAUUUAUCAAGAAUCAACACUGUACAAAUAUCUCAGAACUUUCUAACACAUCUGAAAAUGAUGAGCAAAAUGCUGAGGAUUUGGAUGAUAGUGAUCUUCCUAAAACAUCUUCUGGAAGGAGGAGAGUCCAUGAUGGGAAAAAAAGCAUCAGAGCUACGAACUAUGUUGAAAGCAACUGGAAGAAACAGUGUAAGGAACUAGUGAACUUAAUUUUUCAGUGUGAAGAUUCUGAACCAUUUAGACAACCUGUUGAUUUGGUUGAAUAUCCAGACUACAGAGAUAUUAUAGAUACCCCAAUGGAUUUUGGAACAGUAAGGGAAACUCUAGAUGCGGGAAAUUAUGACAGCCCUUUGGAGUUUUGCAAAGACAUCCGGCUGAUAUUUAGCAAUGCAAAAGCGUAUACACCAAACAAAAGAUCAAAGAUUUAUAGUAUGACCUUGAGAUUAUCUGCCUUAUUUGAAGAAAAAAUGAAGAAAAUCUCUUCUGAUUUUAAAAUUGGUCAAAAAUUCAAUGAAAAACUUCGAAGAAGCCAGAGGUUCAAGCAACGGCAAAAUUGUAAAGGUGACAGUCAGCCUAACAAAAGUAUCAGAAACCUCAAGCCGAAGAGGUUAAAAUCUCAGACAAAAAUAAUUCCUGAGUUGGUAGGUUCUCCUACCCAGUCUACCUCAAGUAGGACAGCUUAUCUUGGAACCCACAAGACAAGUGCUGGUAUCUCUUCAGGUGUUACUUCUGGUGACUCUUCAGAUUCAGCAGAAUCAUCAGAAAGGAGGAAAAGAAAUAGACCUAUAACAAAUGGUUCUACAUUAUCUGAAAGUGAAGUGGAAGAUUCUUUAGCUACCUCUUUGUCAUCGUCAGCUUCCAGUAGUUCUGAGGAAAGCAAAGAGAGUUCCAGAGCUCGUGAAUCCUCCUCACGCAGUGGGCUAUCCAGAAGCAGCAAUCUCAGGGUAACCAGAACUAGAGCUGCUCAAAGAAAAACUGGUCCCGUUUCAUUAGCAAAUGGAUGUGGCAGAAAAGCCACUCGAAAGAGAGUCUAUUUAAGUGAUUCUGAUAACAAUUCAUUGGAGACUGGUGAAAUUCUAAAAGCCAGAGCUGGAAAUAACCGAAAAGUCUUAAGGAAGUGUGCUGCUGUGGCUGCCAAUAAAAUAAAGCUAAUGAGUGAUGUAGAAGAGAAUUCUAGCUCUGAAAGUGUCUGUUCUGGUCGGAAGCUGCCUCACCGCAAUGCUUCUGCUGUAGCUAGAAAAAAGUUAUUACAUAAUUCUGAAGAUGAACAGAGCUUAAAGUCAGAAAUUGAAGAAGAGGAGCUAAAAGAUGAAAAUCAACUAUUACCAGUGUCCAGUUCUCACACUGCCCAGAGCAAUGUUGAUGAAUCUGAAAACAGAGACUCAGAGUCAGAAAGUGAUUUGCGGGUAGCCCGGAAAAAUUGGCAUGCUAAUGGUUACAAGUCCCAUACUCCAGCACCUUCAAAGACAAAAUUUCUUAAAAUAGAGUCUUCUGAGGAAGACUCUAAAAGUCAUGAUUCAGAUCAUGCAUGUAACAGAACUGCUGGCCCAUCAACGUCUGUGCAGAAACUUAAGGCAGAGAGCAUCUCAGAGGAAGCAGAUUCUGAACCAGGAAGAUCUGGUGGUAGGAAAUACAAUACAUUUCACAAGAAUGCGAGUUUCUUUAAAAAAACCAAGAUUCUGAGUGACUCAGAAGACUCUGAAUCUGAAGAGCAAGAUAGAGAAGAUGGGAAAUGUCAUAAAAUGGAAAUGAACCCAAUUUCAGGAAAUCUGAACUGUGACCCUAUUGCUAUGUCCCAGUGUUCCUCAGAUCAUGGAUGUGAAACUGAUUUAGAUUCAGAUGAUGACAAAAUAGAAAAACCAAACAAUUUUAUGAAAGAUUCUGCAUCACAAGACAAUGGACUAAGCAGAAAAAUUUCCAGGAAAAGGGUCUGUUCCAGUGACUCAGACAGUAGUUUACAGGUGGUUAAGAAAUCAUCAAAAGCCAGAACAGGUCUCCUGAGGAUUACUCGAAGAUGUGCAGCUACGGCUGCCAAUAAGAUCAAGCUCAUGAGUGAUGUAGAAGAUGUCAGUUUAGAAAAUGUGCACACUAGAAGCAAAAAUGGAAGGAAAAAACCUCUCCAUCUUGCUUGUACUACAGCUAAGAAGAAAUUGAGUGAUUGUGAAGGAAGUGUACAUUGUGAAGUACCAAGUGAACAGUAUGCCUGUGAAGGCAAGCCACCUGAUCCUGACUCCGAAGGUAGUACAAAAGUGCUUAGUCAGGCUCUAAAUGGAGACUCAGACUCUGAAGAUAUGUUGAAUUCAGAACACAAGCACAGGCAUACCAAUAUUCACAAAAUAGAUGCACCUUCUAAAAGAAAAAGUUCCUCUGUUACAUCUUCAGGAGAAGAUUCAAAAAGUCAUAUUCCAGGGAGUGAGACUGAUAGGACAUUUUCUUCAGAGUCAACCUUGGCACAAAAAGCUACUGCAGAGAAUAAUUUUGAAGUGGAACUGAAUUAUGGGCUGCGCAGGUGGAAUGGCAGAAGACUCAGGACCUAUGGAAAGGCUCCUUUUAGUAAGACAAAAGUGAUUCAUGAUUCACAGGAAACAGCAGAGAAGGAAGUAAAAAGGAAGAGAUCGCAUCCUGAAUUGGAAAAUGUGAAAAUCUCUGAAACAACUGGGAAUUCAAAGUUUAGACCUGAUACUAGUUCCAAAUCAUCAGAUUUGGGAUCUGUAACUGAAUCAGAUAUUGACUGUACUGAUAAUACAAAAACCAAAAGGAGGAAAACGAAAGGAAAAGCAAAAGUAGUUAGAAAAGGUAAAACUUUUACAGCUAACAUAUCUAAAACUGUGAGACGUCAAAGACAAAGCAAACGCCCUAGGUUAAGUGUGGAUGAUAAUGACUGGGAGGAUUUGGACUAUGCAAAAUCUAAAAGAGUUCUUCGACGUUCAAAAAUAAAAACGAGAAAUCAGGGUAGAAGGACUGUGAGAUACCAUGAUGGGGAUGAUGACAGAAGUUUAGAAAAUGUGUUAGAUUUCAAUGGUUGCACCUUAUGACCUUGAGGGAAAGCCAGUUCAUUUAAGAGGAAAUGGACUGGCAUUUAUGGUGAAAGCUGGCUGUUAAAAUUAUUUUUUUGUCUUACAAUUCAGGGAAUAUAUUUAUAUUUUUCUAUGAAAAGUUAUGAAUGUGACUAAAUCAUGACUGUUAUUUUUAUUUGCACUUGCUGGUCUUUGUAGCAGCAUUCAGCACAGGUGCCAAAAUAUGCUUCAUUUUGGGGGCAGAUCUAUUUUGACAGUAUUUGACUACAUAUAGCAAGAGUUUGAAAUAUGUUAAACACUAGACAUCCUGGUUAUCAAAACCAAUGAGCAUUACUUUCAUGGCAGCAAGUGUCAUGCAGUUAUUUUCUGAAUUUGUCAAAGAGGCAGUAGUUUCUAACCCCUGUUCUAUAGUAGUUACAACAAUUUCACAACCUAUGUUUACAGAUUCUUCAUAAAUACAUGCAUACUGACACUAUAAUCAUGGGAGGUGUAACCAUGAUUAGUAGGCGAGGUACCUACCACUUUUUUUUUUUUCUUCCCCUGGCUACUUGAGUAGAAUGCAUUAUACCAGAUCUGGUCACUUUCAUUGAAAUGGUUUCUAAUUUUCUUCCCAAGUGCUGUUGGGUUUUUUUCUUCUUAAGGAAAACGUUGUCACUUUUAUGUUAUAAACUUGAAUUUAUAAAGUGCUGGUAAAUUAUUUUUAAUGAUUUGAGUGCAUGUUUUAAACCUCUAGGACCAGAGCAUAGUCAGAGCAUUUUCUUUUAAAUUGUGCACUAACAAAAUGCUAUAUAAUCUGUCUUCUGUCCAAGAUCUCCUGGUUUCCAUUGUAAGGGAUUUAACCAAAAUCUUGCUCUUCCAUAAUCUUACUCUGUGAAAUAGAGGAAUUCGUGUGCCUUAGAUUUAGAAGUGUGUUCUUUAAUAGAGUGUACAGGGCUAAAAGAGUAUUUAAGUUAAUAUGUAGGUUUCCCCCAUCUGUAUUCCAAUUGUAGAGGUGAGUUUUGUUAAGAGUACAAUUGCAAAUCUUAUCUAUAUAGGAAAAUAGCUAAAUGUCAUUCUCCAUCUCUUUGUUUUAGUUUACUGCUUCCAUGUGCAAUCCUAAGCAUUCUUUGCUGGGGCAACUAAAUGUAUCUUUAUUAGUGACUUCUAGUCCAAAUAUAAGAAACUGUCAUGUUUUGUGGGAAAAUAAUUUUAUAAUCCAUUUAAAGUGAAAGUUUAUCACACAAAUAGUACACUUAUUUUCUAACCAAAUACUUGAUAGGUUAUGCUACUCCAGUGUAGAUGGCCAUUCCUAACUUGUUUGUGCCUGAAGAUGGACUUGAUUCAAAUGGUUUACAUAUUUAGUGGGUAAGGGAUAUGUUACAGUACCCCACCUGUAAGUUAUUUAUUAGCCCUAAUUGUGUUUGAUUUCAGACAAAAUUAACCCUUUUCUCCUGUGUAUCUUUGAAGUGGCAGAUAAGGUGAAGCAUCAGACUGGUAUCAAUAUUAGACAAUGUUAUUUAUUAGCCCUAAUUGUGUUUGGUUUCAGACAAAACCUUUUCUCCUGUGUAUCUUUGAAGUGGCAGACAAGGCGAAGCAUCAGACUGGUAUUAAUGUUAGAGAAUGUUCUGAAGUGUUCCUAUUUUGUAGUUAUCUAUUCCAUUUGACAUAGUAGAAGGUACAUUUUCUUUCUACUCUGAUGCAUGGGGAAGGAUGUUUUUGGACAUUAUCAACUGAGAUAGGUGGGAAACCUCCUCUCAUUUGUGGCUUAGAGAGCUAUCACCAUUUCAGAACUAUGAUGCUUUUCUUCUCAGAACUUGUGUUAAGUAGAUAGUAAACAGAUUGAUUCAUGAUAAUUGUCCUUGACUAAGACUGAAAAGACUAAUGGGAUGCCUUUUACUUUGCUAAUUUUAAAAACUGGUGAUAGAUGUCAAAUCCAUUAAUUUAUUUAAACUCUUCUUAACCUUCUCUUUUAUAAUCUGUUCUCAGGUUUUAACUCCAUGUUUACCAUCAUUUGCAAAAAGGUACCAAAAAAAUCCAUAAAUAAAUAUGGAAUACAUUCAUAAGUACAUACAUUCUUUUGGUAUAAAACAAUAUUUUGACAGUUUAGGCUUCAUUAAUAGAACUAUUCUGAUUAUUUGGACUGCAUUAAUUGGUCAUUGACUGGCCAUCCAAUUACCAUUUUUUCUUUCAGUCCAAAAUAGUUAGACCCUUGCAUACAGAAGUGGUAUUUUGGUUUUUAAUCAGAUUUGGUUUCAUCAGAAGCAGCAAGAAUGGACCUGAUGUCUUUAAAAGCAUAGCCGACAAUGGUAGCUUCUCAAGUUAUGAAAUAAAACUGAGAGAUAAUGGAGAAAAUAAUUUUUAUGGGUUUUUUUGGUUAUGGUGCUAUUCCUAAGGUUAACUUUGAAUAUGUGACACACACACUCCUAAGUACCUUUAAGGAAAAUUAAUAAAUCAUUAAUAGUUAAAAUGUUUACAUUGAGCACUAGAACAUGUUUGGCCUUUUUUUUCUACGUUAUGCAAAAUGCCCAGGGAUUUAAUGCACAGGUGUACUUUAAUGUUUAGGGUCAGUUUGUAGUAUUCUUGAGAAAAAGAUAAAGGGUUAUAAUUUGAAUGUGAACUGAUCCAGAAAUAAGUGCUGUACCUUUCCACUGCACUUGAAGUUCAACUUAAUGGUGUAUGUGAAAAACAAAAACUACUUUGGUUGUGUAUGUCCAAAGUCCUAUGGUUUUAUUCAUUUAUGGUUUUACAGGCUUUGAAGUACUCAGAUUUGAUUUUUGCUUUCUUGGAAAGACUCACUUUACCAAGCAUAUAAAGGAAAAAUGAUUUCAAACAUUGACAAGAUAGAUGAGUGUUAACAAAGCUUUCUUUUUUCGUGUCCUCCUUAUUUAAAAAGGUAUACUUACAAUGUGAAGUAACUUAUGAAUAAAAGGAAAAGUUUAUCCCAUAUUCAAAUAAUUCCUAAGGUCAGCCUCCCUUUUUGUAAGUGGCAAAUAUCUGAUUAAAUCAUUUCUCAGUUUAUUAAUCCUUGGAAACAAUGAUAUAGCAGUUACUCACAGCUUGUAAAUUACAACAGAAAGGUUCCUUUCAAAUAGUAGAGCUGCACCUAAAGAGGAAAUUGGGUUUAUAAGAAAAUGGAGGCAAAGAACUUAAGUUUUAAGAAAAAGCACUUCAAAACAGAAGGGCAAAUGGAAAAGGGGAAUAUAAAACAAACCAAUAAAAAUACCAUCUGAGGGUGUUACUGUCCAAAAGUAAAGAAUAAGAUGCAUCACUAAGCCCUUUGCACUCGUUAUGACCUCGUAAGUAAAAAUUAUCACUUAGAAUAAGGGGUGCACACUACAUUCCCUCUGUCUUCUAGACUUUUUUUUUUGUAGAAGAAUCAGAAAACAAUUUACUAACCUCCCUGUUUGAUAUUAAAAAUAGGAAGAAUUUUAAUAUUUUCUGUUAGUACAAGUUGAACUUGAUUGUGCCAACUGAAACCCCAGAGGUUUGUAUAUCAGUAGAAUGCAAGAACAUUGUUAAAGGUGCUUACGAUCUUUUUUGUUUUCCUUUCCACUCCAUUGUAUCAAUUUUUUGAGUAACUUUUAAAUGGCUAGAAAAUGGUCUUUUUGCUUUGCCCUUUUAAAGCUGAAAUAACCAGCUCCAUUCUUUUCAUGAAUAGUAAGUUGAUAUAUUUAUUUAUCAGGUAUCUUGCAGUUGUCACCAAAUACUGUAGUUUUCUUAUGUUGUAUGGAAAUUAUAGUUCAAUUAUUUUAAUGUGAUAGAGUGCAACAAGUCAUUGUAGAACUUUUCACCUGUUAAUGUUGAAGUUAUACCUCUGAAUUUCUGCUGUGGAUAUCAAGGAAAUAAUAAAGCAGAAACCCCAAGAAAUUUGCAACUUAACAGUUUGAGACUGUCUCUUAUCCUAGUAUUUGGGAAGAGAAGGAAUAAAUUUGUCAAAACUAGGUGAGAAAAUAGAGCAUUGUGGGAAAAACUGAGUCCAACUAGAUUAGCAAAUGUUAAUUCCUAGCUCAAACUGUGAAUAGUAAGGAUUGAAAAGUAAAGUAUGUAAUGCUAAGGGCUGUGUUGUCUUUUCUUACGAUUUUAAGUUUUAAAGGCUGUUAAAUUACAGAGAUGUUGCCCAAGGAUACAUGGGGAUUCUCAAAAGUAAGAGAUUUUUACCUUUUUCAUAAUCUGCCAAGCUGGUUCCUAAUAUAUUGUUAAAUUGGUAGAAAAAUAUCUUUAAAUUGGUGUCUGCUCAAGAAUUGCUUUUCUAGAUUUGAUGGAGGGAGGGGGAGAGUCACAUCAUUUGGAUUCUACCAAUCUGCAGGCUCUAUCUUUGGCAACAUGUAAAUAAUUAGACUAUACAUCUGUUUCUCAAGUAUGGCAAGACCAAUAGUUUGAAUUUAAUUAUCAAUGCUAUGGUAUACUUUCUGGUCAUAUUUUAGUUAUGUCAGUUUUAAGGUAAGUUUUUUCAUUUAUUAAAGCCCUUAAAUGAGAUUUUAGACUGCCAAAGAGAAGAGGCAGUCCAAUUGACCUAACUGAAAUGAGAUGACCAGUAUAUAGAGCCUAGAUGGACUGUAGCAGCUCUACCCCUUUGUUUUACAAGGUAAAUCAUUUUAAAAAUUACCUUUUUUGAUCAGUGGGUAAAAGUUAAAGGGAUCUUUAAUUUUUGAUAUAUUCAAGUUAAUUUUCUAAAUGUGAAUCAGUCCUUGGACUGCAACUAUAUAUUCACCUACAAAAUCCCAAUCAAAAAAUUACAUGAGCCUGUCAAGCAGAUCUUUAGUUUUCCACUUCACAUAAGAUCGUUAAUGUUCUAAAUUAAUCUAUUCAUUUAGAUGAUUUUUGUCAGUUCUUAAAUGGGAUAUAAUAAAUUUAGCAUUUUCAUCUUAACAAGCAAAAGAGUUAAAAAACAAAACAAAACACUACUCCAAGCCAAAUACAUUCUAGCUGGUUAAUUCCAGACUUGUCCCAAGUGGUUCCCCAACCUCUUUUCCACUGGUAAUUUCUUUUCAUGCAGGCAGAAUAUAGGGGUGCGAGCGCUGUGAGUUUUACAUAUGAGCUUGGAUAGGGGAACUGAAGCGAGUCAGGAGCCCUGCUGGAAAAGGGGUUUGCCAUUGGAUUGUCUGUGGCCUGGUUUCUUUCCAGUAGUACAGUAAUAGGGUAGAUUGAAAACAAGUAUUUACUUCUGAUUCUGCCUGCAUUUAGUGUGAAAUGCUCUUAAGGUAUUGCUUCUAAAAAGCAAAUUAAGCAGUUAAGUAUAAAGUCCCUGAAUUCAUAUUUCAAAAUAAGGCUUUUAUGAGAUUUUUAUUAAAAAUUGCAAUAGCCAUCACAAAUCUGAGUUUUUCUAGGGGUGAGAGAAAACUGUAUUGUGAUGAGCUAGAUUAGUUGUAGUUCCAGAAUAAGAACAAAAAUUCAGAGUUGUGUGGUGCCCAUCAUUGAGUAAAUGAACCCUAAAAAUGAAUAAGCUAAUGAACUAGUUCAUGGAAUUAUUUCUGAUGGUCUUUUGACCUGAUGCUGCCAUACUGCAGUGUUACCAGCUCCCCCUAGAAAACGGAACUGUUUAAAAACACAGCAAGUUACAGAAACCAUUUUAUUCUACAGCCAUUGGGGUACUUCAGUUUAUGGGAUGUUUUUGGAAACUUCUGCUUUGGGAGGGAUGAAGAUCAUUGAUAAAUGUUAUUUGCUUUCUGAGUUUUGGGGUCAUUUCAUUGCUUAUCAAUGAAGGGCAGACAGAGGAGAGAAUAUCUCAAGUCUUUUCUGAUAAAAGGCUUGCUUGAGGGAGCUUAUAACUUGCACCUAGAGGGUUUACCCACUUUGUGGAUUUGAUUUAUCCACCAACCACAGCAACCAAUAAUGUCAAGAUUCUAGGAGUUUAUGAAAGAGGCUAGUAUGUUUUCAUUUUGAGUCAGACAUUCUUUUCUCAUUCUCAAAUCUGUUUUAAAUGCUCCAAUUUUAAAAAUGCCAAUGAAAAUUUUAUAAUGCUUCUGUAGUAACCAUAUGCAGUUUACUUUGAAUUUAGGAAAACAGUUUUGUAUGAUGAAAUAUUGUGCAGAAUCUGUAAAUAAGGUAGCUUAAAAAUUAAAAAAAAGUCUAAUUAGAAUAUGAUUAAUCCUUGAAAUGUAGAAACUAGAGAUUGUGUUGAGUCAGAACUGUUAUGUUUGUAUCCAGGUUUCUAUUCACCACAUAUACCAUCUUAGAAUACACACAUAUCUGUGAGUUAUAAUUUAAAGUGGUCAUCCAGGGAAAUGAUCAUGGAGUGCUACUACAGAUGUACAGUUUUACACUACUGAUGUGUUCUUGCCAUACCCAAGUAGGGAAUCACUUCCAGGAAAACAAGUCCUCAAGCACUCAAUGACUUUGUAAACCCAUGACUGAAACAAGACUCAUCUGAGGCAGUAGGACUGGUGGGAUUCUACUGACUUCUUAGUAUCACAUGGCACCAUCACAAAUGCAUUGUUAGAGCAGCAACAUCCAGAGUUCUUAAGCUUGUACCCUAACACACAAAUUUGACUUCUAACCCUGAAAUAUCCUAUAUAUAUUUCUAAAACUGUUUGUAGUUUUCUUGAGAAAAAGCACUUUAUAAUUUACUCAGUUUUCAGUAAUAAAAUUAACACUGACUUGAAUGUAUUUAAAAAAAUUCUCCACAGUUUUGUCUUCCUCAGAUUGUUUUUAUCCUUAUUCUCUGAAAUUCCUGUUUUAUUGUCUAAGACUUAAGAGAUUCAGCUUUAUCAAGUUAGAGUACAGUGUAAUUCAAAUUCUCCCUCCCUUGGGCAUAGUUACUGAAGUUCAAAUUUCCUUAAGUAUUUUUUAAAAACCUGAUUUUAGUUUUUUUUUUCCUGCAGAAUCUUAACUUUUCCAUUAUUCUGGAUGACAAAUAAACAUUUAUUAAAAUGUGUUAGAAUUAGUAUUUACUAGGUUCCUAAAUUGUCAGUAUAGGUACUUUGAUCACACAUCAAAAUGGAAUUUCUGCAACUUAAAGCAUUUUGUUACAAAUUGUAGUUGAAAUAGAAUUUUAUCUAUUUGUCUGGAUGAAUAGGUUGUUGGGAAUGAACCAGUUAUCUGUUCUUUUCUUCCAAAUGCAAAUGGUGCAGCUAGUUGAUAAUAGUAUAUUCUCAUCCUACUAUAAAGUGCAAAUUUCACCUUAAUUUUGCAUAUUUUAAAAUUUUUGUUUACCCUUUGUAGCAUAUUUACAUUUUAGCAUUUGCUAACAUUGAUUUAAUGUGUUAAAGAUUCAUUUUGGAUAUAGGGUUGACUUGUUGGAGAUACUAGUUCAUAAUUUUAAAAUUCCCAAGAGAAGUGUCUUUGAAGUGGUAAACACAGUGCACUUUAAGCCACUUCUCUUCCCACAGAGUCCAGCUGAAGGAGGUAAGGGCAUGCUGCAUGAGAGUAAUGCCGUGAUGAGUGUCUUACUCUGGUAAAAUGCCAUUUACAAUGCCUGGAGACUGAACACUGAACAAAACAUAGUGCCCUUAGAAUUUCACUGGAAAAACAUGUGAAUCACAUAAGUUAGUUGGCAAAAGGAACUGAUGUGUAUGUGGUGGGGUUGCUUUGAAUAAAGUAUUUCCUAACCUAUUCUGGGGAGAACGCUCAACUGAUCUUAGAGAAGUGUGAAAUCAGUUUCAUAGACUUAGGGAAAAAUCUGAAGUGCUUGCACUGUGAGGGCAGAGGCCUGCCUCAUUAGUCUAGCUGUAUGAACAUGUCAGUCCACAGAAGCAGUUUUUACCUGUACUCAUCUGCCCUUCAGUCAGCUUUGUGACAGAAGGGCAAACAUCUUCACAGAAGAAAAAGUUCAGAAGGUUGGCAUUGGUGGUUUCAUUGCUACAGAAUAAUAGUGUUACUUGAUAGUAUCUGACUAAAAGAGCUCUCAUUUUCUAGUACUUAGUAGUAAAAAGAAUGUGGUGGAGUCCUCCAGAUGUCUAGUGUGGGUGGAGGAUAUCAACUGGUUAUUUCAGUGAUCUACAGCCUUACCUUUUGAAUGCUAAAUGUCUGGAAACUUCAGGCAGGGUCCUACAAAACAAACUGCCAUCAAGAUUGGUGUGUACCAUGAAGGCAGUUUUAGAUAGUUUGACUGUUCAUGGCUGCAAGAAAGACCUAAAAUUCAAGGGCCCGUGAACUUCAGAUACGUAAAAGGAAUAUCACUUCUGUUCUAGAAGAGUACUAAUUAGACUUGUUUGUGAAAUUUGAAAAUUUGGCUUUGAGACACUGGUAACAAACAUAUCUGAGCCCUCCUAAGUUUGGUCAGCACGGAGUAGUAGCUCUGGCAUCAUGUGGCUGUGUAGAGCUCCAGUGUGAUUUCAAGCCCCCUCUAAAAACUGCCUUAGUCUGCAUGAAGUAGUUAACUCUCCAAAGUGCUUUUUGUCUGGCAAAUCCCUUCACAAUUUUCACCUCUCGUCUAAAAGCUUCCUUAAAGGAAGCCUUCCUUGAUCCCUUAGGCUAGGUUAGGUUUCCAGUCUGUGUUCUCAUAGCACUCUGCACUUUUUGGUUCCUUAAAGCAACUCUGUGUUAUUUUUUAGAAUUUUAAUCUGAAUCUCGUGUGUCACAUACCUAGGUCAGAAAAUACUGGAACAAUGAAGUUAAGAUUUAGUAAUUCAAAUUAUGUAAAAUGCUCAUAUAUAUGUUUUUAGAUUAGCAGCUUUAUGAUGCCGAUGCUGAAGGAACUUUUCACCCCAUUCUUACAAGUCUGCUACUGUUUUAAGUGACAUCCUUAUAGUUGUAGAUAAGCAAAUGUAAGGUUAUAUCAAUGUGAAGAAGCCCUUAGUAUCACAUUUUAAAAUUUAUCAUUUAGCAAUAUGACUUUUAAAUUUAUUGUUUCCGAAUGAGUGUUGUUGAGGAAUGUUAGCAGUAGUAAAAUCUUGUGUUACAAGAUUUUUGCAUUUACAUGAACUUUCACUCAUUUUUCAGAAUUUGUUCCUAGAGACAGAGAACCCAAUACAAAAGUGAGAACAUGUAUGCAUAAUCAGAAGGAUGCAGUGCAGAUGCCUAGUGAAACUCUGAAAGCAAAAAUGGUACCUGAGAAAGUUCCCCGCAGAUGUGCUACUGUUGCUGCAAAUAAAAUAAAGAUAAUGAGUAAUCUAAAAGAAACGAUCUCAGGACCAGAAAAUGUCUGGAUUAGGAAGAGUAGCAGAAAACUGCCCCAUCGAAAUGCUUCUGCUGCGGCUAAGAAAAAAUUACUGAAUGUUUAUAAAGAGGAUGAUACAACCAUAAAUUCUGAAAGUGAAAAAGAGCUAGAAGAUAUUAAUAGAAAAAUGCUUUUUUUAAGGGGGUUCAGAUCCUGGAAAGAAAAUGCACAAUAGUGACUAUGAGAAUGUAGAAGUGGCAUCUGAAAACAAUUGGUACACAAGUAAACUGGCAGUUACAUUCUGCUCCCAGCUCUAAAAUUACUCCCUUAUUGGCAUCUUUGGAGGAAUUUUCUAAAAGCCAUAAUCCAGUGGGUUCCUCCCAGUCAGCUCUUGUACAGACAUGUGCUCUGGGGAAUUCUGAGGAGGAAAUAAAUUGCAGAGUCUGUAGGUGGAGAGGUGGAAAGAAAAGACAAAUGGCCUGCUAUAAGACUACUAUUCCUUUCCAGAAUGCAAGGCCUUGAAGACAUGAUUCCUUAGAGGAAGAAUAUAAUGGGAAGUGUACAGGCUAGGAAGAACUUGAAGUGAACAAAUUUCAAAAUCUUAACCUGAUGCUAAUUUUCAGGGUUCUCCAUUACAGUGUAAAAAUUCAGACCACGACAACUAUGGUGUCAUGAGGAAAAAAAAUCAGGCAUUUUUCCAAAGGAAGUGCUAAUGGGCCUAUUUGACUUCUGAGUGAAGCAAAAACUACCCAGAUCCAUUCCCUACAAUUCACAUCCCCAAAGGUCAAAAACAAACUAGGAGGACCUGGGAAUUUCAGCUGGAGAUACUGAUUAUUGAGUUCUGAAGUAGAGUGUUGGAAAUAGGCAAUUAGAGAAAGUCCAUUGAUGUCAUUUUGUUUAUAAUAUUGCAGUUCAUACUGAAUGACCACUUGAUAUGACUAAUUCAGGGAAUAUAUAUUUUUCUAUGAAAGCUAUGAAUGUUACUAUCACGGCUUUUCCUUAUUUUUACUUGUAUGUAGCAGCAUUUACAGAAAUGCCAAAAAUGUGCCUCAUUAAGAGGCAGGUCUUAAUCAGUUAGAUAAAAAUAAAAUGUAUAGCUUAAGAUCAAAACAGUCAUAUUUUUAGAUACAGUGAAAUCUUUUAUGUUUCUCUACAGCACCUUAAAAAUUAGAACUUGAAUACUUUGAGUAAACUUACUACAAUCUCAUCCCAACAAACUUUAAUGGUAGCAUGUUUGGCCUAUUUCAUUGUGGCCUGUACUAGGAUUAGAAAAUUUGGUCGUGGUAUAACAAAGAAGUGUAUUUACAAUAGGAUUUAAUUUGUUGUUAAUAUGUAUUUGUUGAAAUUAAAAUUGCCAGAUUAAAUGAAUAUACUGUCGCAUCUUUUUAACAUAGUAACGUGUUACUGGAAAAAUUAAGUUGUUGAAAGUAAGUUGUUUUCCCAUUUAAAAAUAUCUGAAUAUAUGAUUUGCAUGUGUAAAUCUGAAAAACUAAACUACAGAAACCUAGGGUUUUCUAUUUCUUUUUUAAGUCAAAUGCAUUUUUUUUUUUUUGUUAUACAGAUGAACCAAGUGUCUAAAAUACUUGAGAAAUUUGUGGUUGCAUGUCUGUUUUAAAAAAAAGGCUUUUUGUUUUUUAGCAUAAGCCAGAAUAUUCUAACCUACUAAGUCUGUGUCCUUUGCUCCUUUUGUAGUAUACUUUCAUCUAAAUUACUGAUCCCCAAUAUGUUGAUACACAGGUGAGAAAGGGAAGAAUUCCUAAUAAACUGCUAUUACUUUUA